GACAGGCUGCGCCCGCCCGCGCCCGGGGUGAUGCAGUUGCCCCCCGCGCUGUGCGCCCGCCUCGCUGCGGGGCCCGGGGCGGCGGAGCCGCUGCCUGUAGAGCGGGAUCCCGCGGCUGGGGCCGCGCCCUUUCGCUUCGUUGCGCGCCCCGUGCGCUUCCCGCGGGAGCACCAGUUCUUCGAGGAUGGGGACGUGCAGCGCCACCUCUACCUCCAGGACGUGAUCAUGCAGGUGGCCGACGUGCCUGAGAAGCCCAGGGUGCCCGCGUUUGCCUGCCAGGUGGCCGGCUGCUGCCAGGUGUUCGAUGCCCUGGACGACUACGAGCACCACUACCACACGCUGCACGGAAAUGUUUGCUCCUUUUGCAAGCGGGCCUUCCCUUCCGGACACCUGCUGGACGCCCACAUCCUGGAGUGGCACGAUUCGCUCUUCCAGAUCCUGUCUGAGAGGCAGGACAUGUAUCAGUGCUUGGUAGAAGGCUGCACAGAGAAGUUCAAGACCAGCAGAGACCGGAAGGAUCACAUGGUGAGGAUGCACCUGUACCCCGCGGACUUCCGGUUUGAUAAGCCAAAGAAAAGCAGAAGCCCAGCCUCAGCAGAAGCCCCAGGGGACAGUGGAGAGCGGUCAGAAGGGGAGGCCAUGGAAAUCUGCUCUGAGCCUGUGGCAGCCUCCCCUGCACCGGCAGGUGAGAGGCGGAUCUACAGACAUAGAAUACCCUCUACCAUCUGCUUUGGUCAGGGUGCCGCUCGAGGAUUUAAAAGCAACAAGAAGAAAACCAAACAAUGCUGAUAGACUCAGAAAAGGAGUGGGGGGCAGUCACCACUGCUGGGCGUGGCAUCCGCCUUGGGCCUUUCUCCGACCUUCUGGUGUGGCCGCCCUGGGGGCCAGGCCCUCGCCAUCCUCCCCAUCCUUGUUCCUCAGCAAAUGGCAUUAGCAGCUGUCAUCAGAAGCUGUGAGGGACCCACAGAUUUUGGAAACGACCUGGACACACUAUUGGGAAGGAGAUGUGGACGGCCUGUCUCCUCCUGCAGGGCCCACCCUAAGAAUGUAUUUUUAAACACAUGAAAUAAGUAUUUUUCACUGA